AUGGGCUCCGGGCGCGGAGAAACUCCCUCAACAUCCAUCUCCAUCUUCCCAUUCACUGGAGGGCAAGACAAAAGCGGAGUGGAGACUUGGCAGCGGCGCCCGGCAGCUACUCAGCUGCCCGUGGCACGCAUGGCUCGCCGAGGAGGGGCCGCCUCCCGCGCGCCCUCCCUUCUGCCACCCUUCGCCCCCGCUCCCCGCAGCUCCGCUCGCCUGCUUGGCUCCGGCCCUGGCGGCGUCUGGGCCGGGGUGCGCGAGGAGCGGGUGGCCGCGUGUCCUUGGAGCGCUGGCCUUCAGGCGCCCCCGGCAGUCCCGCUAAGCAGAGCGCAUCCCGGCGGCGGCGGCGGCGGCGGCGGCGGCGCCUCCCAGCCGCGCUCCCAGCCUCAGGGCCGCUUGGGUACUUGCUCUCCAGCCCGGCCCACGCUCCUAGCCGCUUUCCAGCGUCUCUUGGGGCCCCUUGGCGUUUCUCCUCCCUACCAACCUUCUGAACAAAGUUGCUGGAAGAACCAACCUGGUCGCCGGGCUUUGCCCGGCGAAGCUGGCAAGAAUAGGGACUCUCAGGUGCAAGUGAAAUCUACCUUCCCCGCCCGCUGACCAAGCGCCGACCCUCAGCCUUACCCCCUCCCCAACGCAAAGGAGCCAAGGAAAGGAGGGAUCUCCGACCUGUGCGAGGUGGUGGCGGCGAGGACUAGAAAGAGAGGAGCGUGCGGAGGGCUGGUGCGCCCACCCCCAACCCCAGGUGACCCCCGCCUCCGCGCUGGCCCUGGUCCCCUCCCUCUCCCGGCCGAGCGCGCCUCCGGGGUCAGUCCCUCCGGGCUGCGCGUGUGUGUAUCCCAGAGCUCCGCUCCGGGGUCUGUUCUGCCGCUGGCGGCUCCGCGCCGCACAGCCCUGCACUAAAGAACUGGAGUAGAGAAGGAGAAGCCAACGGCAAAUUCCGGGCAGGAAGUCGACCUACCCUUGCCUCUGGCCAGGUCGCAGUGUAGCAAUAAAAAUCACAUGUCAGUUCAGACAGCAGCAGGAAUAGCUGACUGGGAAGGAAAUAAUUGGAGGAGUAGUCCCAGCAGUAAGAGAGAAGAAAGAAAGACAUGGGCCUUGGAAGAUAGAUAGGAUAUGAGUAAAAUGAAGCAAAGAGCAUUGCGAUUAGAGCAAGGUGUUGGAAAUGUAUGCUGCAGAAAUACUGCCUAAAACCUGGAAGUCUCAUAGCUGAAAGCACCAAACUUUGGUCCCCCUCUCGCCACCAAAAUGAAGAGAGAAUGCAGCUGGAGAUGAUGAAUUUCAGUGUGGAUGUAGAUGCAGACAUAACAGCCAUUUCAGAAGAGCAUGUUUCACCUAUAAUAUCUGCUAUAACUGAAGUCAGCUGAUCUUGCUUUUAAACCCUUUUAGGAAUUUCAAAAUCAGCUCAAUGGAUAAUGACAAAAGUGUUAACUUCUGUGACACCAUUCUCUAAAGAUGAAACCAUAAUGUCAUCAGGGGUGGUGUUAAAUGCCAGACUGAAGAGAAAGUGGAAGAGACAGAUACGGUGGAAUGCAAGGAUACUGGACCCCUGAGAGCAGCCUGUUGUCAUUGCUUGGCAUUUACAGCAUCUGUAAUUCAUUAGCUAUUCUUUUCUUUUUUAAUGAGGAAACAGAAAGGAGAUCAAGGAAUGAGCUCAAAGCAACCAAAAAAAUCUUUUCAGUAGUAAGAUAAACAAAUGUUACCAUGAGUCUGAAAGCUAGAAUUCUACAAGGGGAAGAAAUAUAUGGCCCCUGCUAAUUUUAACCAGGACCAUUGCCUGUGUAAUUGCCAUAAUAAUAAAAGCUACUGGUAUCUAUAUUUUA